GCUUUUAGGCCUGUUGCCUUCUUUUCUUCAAACCUGCCUGCUUUCUUCUGUCCCUGAGUGUGUGGGCCAUUACUUAGAUUUGACUCCUCCUGCCAAUUUAUUUUUUACUUUCCCUCAUGCAGGACUCAAAUGGAUGCUAAAAAGCCAAGGAAAUGUGAUUUGACUCCCUUCCUGGUUUUGAAAGCAAGAAAGAAACAAAAGUUCACCUCUGCGAAGGGCCCCACUCUUUCUGAGAUCUACAUGGUUGGAAGUAAACUUUCGGUUCAGAUCCAGAAGCCACCUUCCAAUAUCAAGAACUCCAGAAUGACCCAAGUCUUUCAUAAGAACACCAGUGUUACUUCACUCCCCUUUGUGGACACCAAGGGGAAGAAGAAUACGGUAAGCUUCCCACACAUUAGCAAGAAAGUCCUGCUGAAGUCAUCCCUGCUGUAUCAGGAGAAUCAAGCUCACAAUCAGAUGCCGGCCUCAGAGCUCAAGGCUUCAGAAAUACCUUUCCACCCUAGCAUUAAAACCCAGGAUCCCAAGGCAGAGGAGAAGUCACCAAAGAAGCAAAAGGUGACUCUGACAGCGGCAGAGGCCCUAAAGCUUUUUAAGAACCAGCUGUCUCCAUAUGAACAAAGUGAAAUCCUGGGCUACGCGGAGCUGUGGUUCCUGGGUCUUGAAGCCAAGAAGCUCGACACGGCUCCUGAGAAAUUUAGCAAGACGAGUUUUGAUGAUGAGCAUGGCUUCUAUCUGAAGGUCCUGCAUGAUCACAUUGCCUACCGCUAUGAAGUUCUGGAGACAAUCGGGAAGGGGUCCUUUGGACAGGUGGCCAAGUGCUUGGAUCACAAAAACAAUGAGCUGGUGGCCCUGAAAAUCAUCAGGAACAAGAAGAGGUUUCACCAGCAGGCCCUGAUGGAGCUGAAGAUCCUGGAAGCUCUCAGAAAGAAGGACAAAGACAACACCUACAAUGUGGUGCAUAUGAAGGACUUUUUCUACUUUCGCAAUCACUUCUGCAUCACCUUUGAGCUCCUGGGAAUCAACUUGUAUGAGUUGAUGAAGAAUAACAACUUUCAAGGCUUCAGUCUGUCCAUAGUUCGGCGCUUCACUCUCUCUGUUUUGAAGUGCUUGCAGAUGCUUUCGGUAGAGAAAAUCAUUCACUGUGAUCUCAAGCCCGAAAAUAUAGUGCUAUACCAAAAGGGCCAAGCCUCUGUUAAAGUCAUUGACUUUGGAUCAAGCUGUUAUGAACACCAGAAAGUAUACACGUACAUCCAAAGCCGGUUCUACCGAUCCCCAGAAGUGAUCCUGGGCCACCCCUACGACGUGGCCAUUGACAUGUGGAGCCUGGGCUGCAUCACGGCGGAGUUGUACACGGGCUACCCCCUGUUCCCCGGGGAGAAUGAGGUGGAGCAGCUGGCCUGCAUCAUGGAGGUGCUGGGUCUGCCGCCAGCCGGCUUCAUUCAGACAGCCUCCAGGAGACAGACAUUCUUUGAUUCCAAAGGUUUUCCUAAAAAUAUAACCAACAACAGGGGGAAAAAAAGAUACCCAGAUUCCAAGGACCUCACGAUGGUGCUGAAAACCUAUGACACCAGCUUCCUGGACUUUCUCAGAAGGUGUUUGGUAUGGGAACCUUCUCUUCGCAUGACCCCGGACCAGGCCCUCAAGCAUGCUUGGAUUCAUCAGUCUCGGAACCUCAAGCCACAGCCCAGGCCCCAGACCCUGAGGAAAUCCAAUUCCUUUUUCCCCUCUGAGACAAGGAAGGACAAGGUUCAAGGCUGUCAUCACUCGAGCAGAAAAGCAGAUGAGAUCACCAAAGAGACUACAGAGAAAACAAAAGAUAGCCCCACGAAGCAUGUUCAGCAUUCAGGUGAUCAGCAGGACUGUCUCCAGCACGGAGCUGACACUGUUCAGCUGCCUCAACUGGUAGACGCUCCCAAGAAGUCAGAGGCAGCUGUCGGGGCGGAGGUGUCCAUGACCUCCCCAGGACAGAGCAAAAACUUCUCCCUCAAGAACACAAACGUUUUACCCCCUAUUGUAUGACCUUUGCUGAGGGUAUGUCCUGCUCCUUUCCACCAGUGAUUUGUAUUAAGACAGCACUUAUAUUGUACAAUACUUCAGACUGUUUUUUUUAAAUACAUAAAACUUUAUGUUAAAAAACUCUA